AUGAGGAUUGCUGUCCUCCUCUUCGCCAUUUUCUUCUUUAUGAGCCAAGUUCUACCAGCCAGGGGCAAAUUCAAGGAGAUCUGUGAACGUCCAAAUGGCUCCUGUCGGGACUUUUGCCUUGAAACAGAAAUCCAUGUUGGGAGAUGUUUAAAUAGCCAACCCUGCUGCCUGCCUCUGGGGCAUCAACCAAGAAUUGAGAGCACUACACCCAAAAAGGACUGAAGCCUGUUGUUUUCUGGAGGUUUUAUGUUCUCUUUUUUCUCUCUCCCUCUCUCUGUCUCCCUGUCUCCCUUUCCCUCUCUCCAUUUUUCUCACAGGGAUUUUUAUUGAAUCCUCAAAAAAGAAUAAACCAAAACCAACCAGCACAAAA